GUAGGACUCCGGCCUUGGUGGCGGGUGGCUGGCGGUUCCGUUAGGUCUGAGGGAGCGAUGGCGGUACGCGCGUUGAAGCUGCUGACCACACUGCUGGCUGUCGUGGCCGCUGCCUCCCAAGCCGAGGUCGAGUCCGAGGCAGGAUGGGGCAUGGUGACGCCUGAUCUGCUCUUCGCCGAGGGGACCGCAGCCUACGCGCGCGGGGACUGGCCCGGGGUGGUCCUGAGCAUGGAACGGGCGCUGCGCUCCCGGGCAGCCCUCCGCGCCCUUCGCCUGCGCUGCCGCACCCAGUGUGCCGCCGACUUCCCGUGGGAGCUGGACCCCGACUGGUCCCCCAGCCCGGCCCAGGCCUCGGGCGCCGCCGCCCUGCGCGACCUGAGCUUCUUCGGGGGCCUUCUGCGUCGCGCUGCCUGCCUGCGCCGCUGCCUCGGGCCGCCGGCCGCCCACUCGCUCAGCGAAGAGAUGGAGCUGGAGUUCCGCAAGCGGAGCCCCUACAACUACCUGCAGGUCGCCUACUUCAAGAUCAACAAGUUGGAGAAAGCUGUUGCUGCAGCACACACCUUCUUCGUGGGCAAUCCUGAGCACAUGGAAAUGCAGCAGAACCUAGACUAUUACCAAACCAUGUCUGGAGUGAAGGAGGCCGACUUCAAGGAUCUUGAGACUCAACCCCAUAUGCAAGAAUUUCGACUGGGAGUGCGACUCUACUCAGAGGAACAGCCACAGGAAGCUGUGCCCCACCUAGAGGCGGCGCUGCAAGAAUACUUUGUGGCCUAUGAGGAGUGCCGUGCCCUCUGCGAAGGGCCCUAUGACUACGAUGGCUACAACUACCUUGAGUACAACGCUGACCUCUUCCAGGCCAUCACAGAUCAUUACAUCCAGGUCCUCAACUGUAAGCAGAACUGUGUCACGGAGCUUGCUUCCCACCCAAGUCGAGAGAAGCCCUUUGAAGACUUCCUCCCAUCGCAUUAUAAUUAUCUGCAGUUUGCCUACUAUAACAUUGGGAAUUAUACACAGGCUGUUGAAUGUGCCAAGACCUAUCUUCUCUUCUUCCCCAAUGACGAGGUGAUGAACCAAAAUUUGGCCUAUUAUGCAGCUAUGCUUGGAGAAGAACACACCAGAUCCAUCGGCCCCCGUGAGAGUGCCAAGGAGUACCGACAGCGAAGCCUACUGGAAAAAGAACUGCUUUUCUUCGCUUAUGAUGUUUUUGGAAUUCCCUUUGUGGAUCCGGAUUCAUGGACUCCAGAAGAAGUGAUUCCCAAGAGAUUGCAAGAGAAACAGAAGUCAGAACGGGAAACAGCCGUACGCAUCUCCCAGGAGAUUGGGAACCUUAUGAAGGAAAUCGAGACCCUUGUGGAAGAGAAGACCAAGGAGUCACUGGAUGUGAGCAGACUGACCCGGGAAGGUGGCCCCCUGCUGUAUGAAGGCAUCAGUCUCACCAUGAACUCCAAACUCCUGAAUGGUUCCCAGCGGGUGGUGAUGGACGGCGUAAUCUCUGACCACGAGUGUCAGGAGCUGCAGAGACUGACCAAUGUGGCAGCAACCUCAGGAGAUGGCUACCGGGGUCAGACCUCCCCACAUACUCCCAAUGAAAAGUUCUAUGGUGUCACUGUCUUCAAAGCCCUCAAGCUGGGGCAAGAAGGCAAAGUUCCUCUGCAGAGUGCCCACCUGUACUACAACGUGACGGAGAAGGUGCGGCGCAUCAUGGAGUCCUACUUCCGCCUGGAUACGCCCCUCUACUUUUCCUACUCUCAUCUGGUGUGCCGCACUGCCAUCGAAGAGGUCCAGGCAGAGAGGAAGGAUGAUAGUCAUCCAGUCCACGUGGACAACUGCAUCCUGAAUGCCGAGACCCUCGUGUGUGUCAAAGAGCCCCCAGCCUACACCUUCCGCGACUACAGCGCCAUCCUUUACCUAAAUGGGGACUUCGAUGGCGGAAACUUUUAUUUCACUGAACUGGAUGCCAAGACCGUGACGGCAGAGGUGCAGCCUCAGUGUGGAAGAGCCGUGGGAUUCUCUUCAGGCACUGAAAACCCACAUGGAGUGAAGGCUGUCACCAGGGGGCAGCGCUGUGCCAUCGCCCUGUGGUUCACCCUGGACCCUCGACACAGCGAGCGGGUGAGAGCAGCUCGAGCGGGUGAGAGCAGCUGGUGCUGUGGUGACCCGUUCCCAGAGCGCCCUUGGUUUGCCUUUCUCUUCCCCAAAUCCCAUUGCCAGUGGCUGAGACACGAAAGGAGCACUUGGGACACCAGCUCCAACGCCCUGUCAUUAUGGUCACAUUGCCUUGUCCUCCCUGGGCCUGCUGUGAACGGGAUCCAGGUGGGGAAAGAGGUCAAGACAGGGAGCGAUGCUGAGUUCUUGGUUCCCUCCUUGGGCCCCACUUCAGCUGUCCUUUUCCAGAGAGUAGGACCUGCUGGGAAGGAGAUGAGCCUGGGGCCAUUAAGGAACCUUCCUUGUCCCCUGGGAAGUAGCAGCUGAGAGAUAGCGAGUGUCUGGAGCGGAGGCCUCUCUGAAUGGGCAGGGGUUUGUCCUUGCAGGACAGGGUGCAGGCAGAUGACCUGGUGAAGAUGCUCUUCAGCCCAGAAGAGAUGGACCUCUCCCAGGAGCAGCCCCUGGAUGCCCAGCAGGGCCCCCCCGAACCUGCACAAGAGUCUCUCUCAGGCAGUGAAUCGAAGCCCAAGGAUGAGCUAUGACAGCGUCCAGGUCAGACGGAUGGGUGACUAGACCCAUGGAGAGGAACUCUUCUGCACUCUGAGCUGGCCAGCCCCUCGGGGCUGCAGAGCAGUGAGCCUACAUCUGCCACUCAGCCGAGGGGACCCUGCUCACAGCCUUCUACAUGGUGCUACUGCUCUUGGAGUGGACAUGACCAGACACCGCACCCCCUGGAUCUGGCUGAGGGCUCAGGACACAGGCCCAGCCACCCCCAGGGGCCUCCACAGGCCGCUGCAUGACAGCGAUACAGUACUUAAGUGUCUGUGUAGACAACCAAAGAAUAAAUGAUUCAUGGUUUUUUUUA